GGGUGUGGGACUGCCGCUCUGCGCGGCGAGAGGUGGCCUGGGAAUGGCCGGGCCGGGGGUGGGCCGGAGCCGCUGUGGCGGCGGCGGCGGCUGGGGGCGGUGAGCGCGGCGUGGGGCUGCCCCUCCCCGGAGGCGGCGGGGGCGGCCGGGGCCGCGCCGCACCGCACCGCGCGGGCGGCCAUGGAGCGAGCCUAGGGCCCGACAGGAACUGUGGAAGGUGCAUCAGUGAAGAAAUGGACCAAUGUGUAUAAUCAUGGAAUCUCCUUGCUAACCAUCACCACCAGCUCUCCUUAAUACAUGAGCAAGAGUGGGUCAGGGGAGAAGGAAAAGAGGUCAACAUGAAGCUAAAGCAGCGAGUCGUGCUGUUAGCAAUUCUCCUUGUCAUUUUUAUCUUCACCAAAGUUUUCCUGAUUGACAACUUAGAUACAUCAGCUGCCAACCGGGAGGACCAGAGGGCCUUUCACCGAAUGAUGACUGGCUUGCGGGUGGAGCUGGCACCCAAGCUGGACCAUACCUUGCAGUCUCCCUGGGAGAUUGCAGCCCAGUGGGUGGUUCCCCGGGAAGUGUACCCUGAAGAGACACCAGAGCUGGGGGCAGUCAUGCAUGCCAUGGCCACCAAGAAAAUCAUUAAAGCUGAUGUGGGUUAUAAAGGGACACAGCUGAAAGCCUUACUGAUACUUGAAGGAGGCCAGAAAGUUGUUUUCAAACCUAAGCGGUUUUUGUGUGGACAUAAAUUUUCAACUCAUUUGGAUAGAUACCAGAAGCAUAAUUGCUGGACCACAUGGUAUAGCCGAGACCAUGUGGUGGAAGGGGAACCGUAUGCUGGUUAUGAUAGACACAAUGCAGAGGUAGCAGCCUUUCACUUGGACAGGAUUCUGGGUUUCCACCGAGCCCCCUUGGUAGUUGGCAGAUUUGUUAAUCUUCGGACAGAGAUCAAACCUGUCGCCACAGAGCAGCUGUUGAGCACCUUCCUAACUGUAGGAAACAAUACUUGUUUUUAUGGGAAGUGCUAUUACUGCCGAGAAACAGAACCAGCUUGUGCUGAUGGAGACAUAAUGGAGGGAUCUGUCACACUUUGGCUUCCAGAUGUGUGGCCUCUGCAGAAGCACCGUCACCCAUGGGGCAGGACUUACCGAGAAGGCAAAUUGGCCAGGUGGGAGUAUGAUGAGAGCUACUGUGAUGCUGUGAAGAAAACGUCCCCUUAUGACUCUGGCCCGCGCCUCUUGGACAUCAUUGACACAGCUGUCUUUGAUUACCUGAUUGGCAAUGCUGACCGCCAUCACUAUGAGAGCUUUCAAGAUGAUGAAGGCGCUAGUAUGCUCAUCCUUCUUGAUAAUGCCAAAAGCUUUGGGAACCCCUCGCUGGAUGAAAGAAGCAUUCUUGCCCCUCUCUAUCAGUGUUGCAUCAUUCGGGUGUCCACCUGGAACAGACUGAACUACCUAAAGAAUGGUGUGCUAAAGUCUGCCUUAAAAUCUGCCAUGGCCCAUGACCCCAUCUCCCCAGUGCUCUCUGAUCCUCAUCUGGACGCCGUGGACCAGCGGCUCCUGAGUGUCCUGGCCACCGUGAAGCAGUGCACCGACCAGUUUGGGAUGGACACAGUACUGGUGGAAGACAGGAUGCCUCUCUCACACUUGUAAUUCUCGACACAAAAUAAGUGAAACUUCUUUUUACAAAGAUAGAGAAACAGCACAAUCAAUUCCAAAUGGUAUGAGAUGGAUUGGAAGUGGCCAGCAGCAAGUUCUGGUGACGGGACAGAGUGGCCUUGGAUGUCUUUGGUAUUUUCUGUAGUAGAAACUAAAGCAAAGACCACAAGUUUCAGAGCAUGGAGACAUUCCUGCUGAAUCGCCUUCUCACCUCCUCGGCAAUUGCUCAUUCUAGGGUUGGGCAUCAUAGUUGGUCAGUCUUAAUUCCCAUGCCAAAGGACAAACAGGUGUGACAUUUGGAUAGAUGAAUACUGGGAUUGGCUCUGGAGCAUGUGUUUUGAGUUGAACCUUGCAGUCCUUUCUCUACGCCCGUGGAUUUUGUGGAAACACUUUGCAAUCUCUUUGUCUUUUUUUUUUUUACCAGAACUAGUUACAUUGGAAUGCUUACUGUCCUACAGAGUGGCAGCAAAUAAAACCUUGCAUUCCAUCAAGCCAAAAUAGCACACUCUGUUAGAGGAGAUACAUGUUUAAGAUAGAAUUGGAGGGAAGGACAAAAACAGAAAAAUGUUUGGGCUUUUAAGCCAUUGGGUAGUAUUGUUUUGAUGAUCUUAGAGGAGGGAAGAAGAGAGAGAGACCCAAUGGUAGAACCAGAAUCAGGGAGAUGACUGAACUACUGAAAAACAGGUUCCCUUGUAUUUAGGAUCUUAAGGUGUAUAAAAAGCAAACAUGACUUUGCACCUAAGUAAAUUCUGCAUUCUCAUAGUUGUGUCCCAAUUAACCAAAAAGUUGUCUCUAGAGAAAAUACUAUUACAAUCUAAGCAUGAUUCUCUGUGGAGACUAAUUUUUUCCCCUUUUGCCAAAAGCAGUCCUUCCCAAAUUAACAAAGCAAACUGAAAUAAUACCUUGAAUAACAGGUUGCCUGUGGUCUCUGUCAUCCUCGUUUCUCUUCUGAAAUGAAUUUCCACCUCUGCCUUUAAGGCAUUUUUGUCACUGAAGCUGCUGUUCCCAAGAGAUCGGCAACCUUUUUGUCCCUUUCUCAUAAGAAAGGGACACUCCUACAGGUGAGAGUGUAUACCUUACUCUCUCAGAUAAGUGGCUGGACUUAUCUUGUGAUUUGGGGCCAUGGAAGAUUGGAAACAAAGAUUUUAAGCCUUCUUCUUUUUUUCUUUUUUCUUUUUUUUUUGAGACCAAGUCUCACUCUGUUGCCCAGGCUGGAGUGCAGUGGCACGAUCUUGGCUUACUGCAACCUCCGUCUCCCAGGUUCAAGCGAUUCUCUUGCCUCAGCCUCCAGAGUAGCUGGGAUUACAGGCGCCCGCCAUCGUGCCCAGCUAAUUUUUAUAUUUUUAGUGGAGACAGGGUUUCGGGUUUCACCAUGUUGGCCAGGUUGAUCUUGGACUCCUGACCCCAGGUGAUCCACCUGCCUCAGCCUUCCAAAGUGCUGGGAUUACAGGCAUGAGCCACCGUGGCCGGCCAAGAUUUUAAGCCUUCUGAGCCUUGAAAUUGAGGAGGUUAAAAGGAAGAGCCUUAAGAUUUUGAUUUAUGUCAAAUCCUAAUUCUAUCAUUCAGUCUUGUUUGGAGUUCUGAACCCAUGAUGUUGUAUUAUGCUUCUUUCUCCUCUUAGCACUCUCAAAUUUCAGGUUUGUAAAACACAGUUUUUGUUUUGUGUUCUGGCAAAGUGAUCUCAACAUGUAAGUAGUUGCAGUAAAACACAGGGGCAAAGGAAGACAGGCCUGAUGUGCCCACUCAUCUAUGGACUCAGAGCUGUGUGCUUUGCUCCUGCAUCUUGUUGAGGUGCUGUUCCAGCUUUGCAUUUCUGUCAAGUAGAGGCGAAUAUAUAAACAGUGUGGUUGAAUACAUUUAAUGCCAGCCAUUGGAAACUAGUUUUAGGCAACCACUCUCAAAAACAGCUUUAGAAUUUAUGCCCAGUUUUCUUGCAUUGAAAGAUAACUGAGUAAUAACCUGUAACUAUUUUUAAAUGGCAUGAAAUUAGGAAACUUUUGUACAUUUUAUAUACAUUUUGAGAUGAACAGAACAAUGGGCUGAGUUAUAAAAAGCGUGUAUUGAAUUUAAGAAGACAGACUAGCACAAAACACAGAAUUCGUGUUAACCAAAGGAGGCAUUGAUUUCAGUUUUAAGGCUACUCAGUGUUGUGUGUCCAGGGAAAUUCACAGCUCAGUAUGAGAAUACCUUGGUUAGUGCUCACCCACAAGCUUCCAGGAGCCAGCUGGGAGGAGACAAUAGGAAGAGAUGUCAUCUCUGCUCUCCCUGUAAAUGUUAGUUGAACUAAGUUAUGGAUUUGUGGUCUUUCAAAUACAUGACGCCUUUAGUAUGCCACACUGAAAUGAAUAAGAAGUCUUCUGAAACUGGGAACUUCAUAACAUUGAAGGCAGAAGAUUCUGCUAAGGAAAAAAGCAGGCAGGAAAGAAAAUGUCUCAUCCUUUCUUGAAAGCAUUUGCAGAAAAUAUAUCAUUUCAUUUUAUUCCCAUCUGUUUUCAAACUCGUGAUCUUAAAAGGCAUUCUGAUGAUAAAUUUAGAAUUUUCAUCUAUAAAAUUUAGAACUCUAAUCCAUAAAGUUAGAAUUGAGCUAAUAGAGUGGUAUGACAUGGCACUAAAAAUAUAAAUUUUUGUUGUAAGUCAGGAUUGGAGUAAGCUGGAAAAGUAUGUUUAGGCAAAUCUUGGAGAAAACCAACCAUAAACUUACAGCUCUAAAAUUCAGAAAGCCCUAAAAUUUCAAACACUGUUUGAAAGAAGAGGUGGGGGCCGGGUGCCGUGGCUCAUGCCUGUCAUCCCAGCAUUUGGGAGGCUGAGGCAGGCAGAUCACCUGAGGCCAGGAGUUCGAGACCAGCCUGGCUGGCUAGCAUGGUGAGACCGUCUCUACUAAAAAUGCAAAAAUUAACAGGGCACGGUGGCAUGCGCCUGUAGUCCCAGCUACUCGGGAGGCUGAGGCAGGAGAAUCACUUGAAUCCAGGAGGCGAAGGUUGCAGUGAGCUGAGAUUGUGCUGCUGCACUCCAGCCUGGGAGACAGAGCGAGACUCUGUCUUAAAAAAAAAAAAAGGAGGUGAAUUUUUUUUUAAGUUUUGUAACACUGUCCUACUUUAUUUAUUAGAAUCUAAGGCUGUUACAAUCAAGUCGUUGCAGGGUUUGGAUCAGCUGUAAGUUAGGUAUGCCUACCAAACAUCCAAAGGUAGACGUGGAGACAUUUUAAUACUACAAAACUAGGAAAAUCAGAACUCAUGGCCAUUUCCUGCCCUCCUCCAACUUGUUAAAACAUGUUUAUUCUAAAGUUCGAAUGGAUAAAUUUGAGUAUAAAGGUUUUGUUAUAAAACUGUUCUUUAGUGUAAGGCUGCAUUGUGGGUUUGGGGGAAAUGUAAAUAAUUUUCUGUGUAAAACAAAUUCAUAGGAUCUGAUUUGCUCAGAGUAUUAUUCAAGAAUGUAUUAAUAAGGCAUUGCCCCCUGUUUGCACUCAGGGUUAAUAUGUCAAAUGAAAUUUAAGAAGGAAAUGGAAGAAUUCAGGUACAUUAAUUGCAUAUUAUUUUGGGAAAGAUGAGUCCUAUACGUGGCAAUUUUUCAAUGUCAUCUGAAGCCAGCAUUAUCUUCCAAAGAAAUCGAUCUUUUUUUUCUAAAAAAAAAAAAUGCUUUUGCCUUCCCUUCCCUUCCCAUCCGCCAUAUUUCUUCAGCCUUUCUUCUCGAUCACCCGUGUAUUCUUUGACCAGUAAAUGACCACACCUCAAUGAUGGUAAAACAGCAUCAUCAGUAAGCUAUCUUAUAUGCCUCAUCCUGUGAGUUUGAGCUUCAGGAAACAUGAGUAAAAGUAUAUGUAAUGUAUAUAGUCGUAUAUGUAUUCUAGCAAGAAAAACAUAUUUAUUUUGACAAAGGGGAACACUGACUUUCUGAAGGAUUCAGAAAGAACCUUAGUGAAAGGUUCUCAGUCUCUGAGAGUGGACCCUAAUUAACAUAAAGACCAUUCAUCAGCGAAUAACUACUGAGCAACUCUAGUGUGCCAGCACAGGCCAGACAUACUAGUGAGCCAGGCACAUCUGGCCUUGGGAAACUCAUCCUACAGGGGAAGGCCAGUUUUUUUCCCUUCAAUUCCUCAAGUCUGGGUGGUGACAAGGUAGGGGCUAGGUACUGGACUACCACAGGUUUUUAGGAACUAAGGUGUUUCUCAUAAACACAAAAUGUUGGGUGAAACUGGGAACAACUACUCAGAAGCUCAUUUAUUUGCUUAAAUGGAAAGUGUGGGAGCCACUACCCUCUCUUUUGAUCUGCCAAGGAUUUCCUCUCAGAGCUGUUGCACAGACAGAGAUUGUACUUGGUAAGAUACCAAACAAGACAGAUAUGGAUCUAAAUUUCUAAUGUGUUCUAUGGGUUUCAAUUCUGAAAAAAGAAAAUGAAUAAAGAUUUUAAUAAAUAUUGA